UUUUUUUUUUUUUUAAGAACGUCUGAGUUCUGAAGCCCAUGUGCUAUGAGAGCUUUUACAUCAAAACAAAAUUCUUUCAUCUCAAGAUCAUUGAAUGUGUAUCUUGAAACUUCAUAUUCAAGGUUGCUUCCAGUCCAUCAACAAUAAUUCCCUACUCUAAUUCCCUACACAGAUUCCUACACUAACCUGCAUACCCUCACGUUCUUGAAGUCAAAGCAGAUUGGAUCACUGACGUUCAACCACUUAAUAAAUCUGAGUAUGUUUGCGUGUCUUGGUGACUUUAACCUUAGUUACAAAACUAGGAGCCUGGCCUAUUUUUUUGGUUAUAGUGUAAGUUUUCUUUCCUUGAAGACUGACUUUUCCAAAACUAUCAAAGGAGAAAGAUGGCAGUAAGGGAGAAAAACAGAGCAUAACUCAGAAACACGAGGCCCAAUGGCAGAGGAAAAAAUGGCCGUUGUUGUCUCAUGAAUAGGCUCUAUUAAUAAGAAUAUUCUGGGUAUCUUUCGUUUGAUGUUAUACAUUUGCGGCAUUUGACAUAAGGAAUUAGGCUUUCGUAAGGGUGGGAUGCCAAGAAAACUGUUGAUACAAAUAGAAAAGCAGUUUGACAGUGUCAUCACCAUGAGAUAACUGAAAUGCAGAUUUAGGGAGCGAAAAUGCUACGGAACAUCUUUCAAAUGUCAAAGCAAAAUGAAGGAAAGAUUGAGUUUGCAGUAAUUAUUUAAGACAUCGUGAAGACUUCUUUAGGACCCAACCAUUUAUCUCCAAAGCAACAUGGCUUUAAAAAUUAAAAUGAGAUCAUUUUGAGAUAACUCUUUUGAUCCCAGUUUAGUCUGGACAGAAAAUUUAAAUAGCCAAAGGGGAAAAAAAAACCAUUAACCAAGAGUUCUGGCUACCGAAAAGAGGCACCAAGAUAAAAUGCAGAACUGGGCCUAACUUUCUUCUCCCUAAAAUAGUUUUGCAACUUGAGUGCAUUCCCCUGGGAAAGAGGCUGUGAAUUCCAUGGAAGUAUGCAUUCCAAGUUUCCUGCCUCUUAGCCCUAAGGUCUACCAACCCCUGGACAAACCUAUCACUCUUCCACACAAGAGGGUCUAUCAAAGCAGUCUGUGGAGAUAUAUAAAAACCAGAGAUCACCAUGCCUUAGGGAGGUGAUGAGCUGACAGGCUGACAGAAACCAUGAAGUUCACAUUUCAAUCCAAGUUUUCCCGUAAAGCCACUGGCUGAGAGGCCCAUCCCUACAUAGGCAGGGAGCAGAGCAGGGAAGACGAAAAUACAAGGUUGAAAAGAAUCAAGUAAGAAGGUGUUUUGUUUUGUUUUUUAGAAUUCUAAAACUUAAAAGGAAUUUUACUGUAACUUAAACUUGCAGCGAUACGAUACGGCCAUGUCAACUUUUGUGGCACUGAAAUGUUACUGCAGGAAUAGCUUCUGGGUUUUAAAAAAUUAUAAGAGAUCAUGAGCAGGAUAAUUAUUUAGCUUUAAAAAUCAACCAAUUAAUAUACAUCUGGAAAUUCACAAUGCUUCGAGCCUUUGUUCAGCCUGGUACGCCUGCAUACCAGCCGCUUCCCAGCCACCUGUCUGCCAACACGGAGGUCAAGUUUAAGGGUACUUUGGUGCAUGAAGCUCAACUCAACUAUUUCUACAUCUCUCCUGGAGAAUCUCCUGUGCGAACCUCUUCUGUGCAGACACCUUCCCACCCAACCUCAACAGAGCCCUGUGGGCCUCCCACGCUGUGUUCCAACUAUGGGAGCCCACGCCCCGCCCAUGCCAACAUGAAUGCCAAUGCGGCAGCGGGGCUGGCCCCUGAGCACAUCCCCACCCCGGGGGCUGCCCUGUCGUGGCAGGCGGCCAUCGACGCAGCCCGGCAGGCUAAGCUGAUGGGCAGCGCUGGCAAUGCGACCAUCUCCACAGUCAGCUCCACGCAGCGGAAGCGGCAGCAAUAUGGGAAACCCAAGAAGCAGGGCAGCACCACGGCCACACGCCCGCCCCGAGCCCUGCUCUGCCUGACCCUGAAGAACCCCAUCCGGAGGGCCUGCAUCAGCAUUGUCGAAUGGAAACCAUUUGAAAUAAUUAUUUUACUGACUAUUUUUGCCAAUUGUGUGGCCUUAGCGAUCUAUAUUCCCUUUCCAGAAGAUGAUUCCAACGCCACCAAUUCCAACCUGGAACGAGUGGAAUAUCUCUUUCUCAUAAUUUUUACGGUGGAAGCGUUUUUAAAAGUAAUCGCCUAUGGACUCCUCUUUCACCCCAAUGCCUACCUCCGCAACGGCUGGAACCUACUAGAUUUUAUAAUUGUGGUUGUGGGGCUUUUUAGUGCAAUUUUAGAACAAGCAACCAAAGCAGAUGGGGCAAACGCUCUCGGAGGGAAAGGGGCCGGAUUUGAUGUGAAGGCGCUGAGGGCCUUCCGCGUGCUGCGCCCCCUGCGGCUGGUGUCCGGAGUCCCAAGUCUCCAGGUGGUCCUGAAUUCCAUCAUCAAGGCCAUGGUCCCCCUGCUGCACAUCGCCCUGCUUGUGCUGUUUGUCAUCAUCAUCUACGCCAUCAUCGGCUUGGAGCUCUUCAUGGGGAAGAUGCACAAGACCUGCUACAACCAGGAGGGCAUAGCAGAUGUUCCAGCAGAAGAUGACCCUUCCCCUUGUGCGCUGGAAACGGGCCACGGGCGGCAGUGCCAGAACGGCACGGUGUGCAAGCCCGGCUGGGAUGGUCCCAAGCACGGCAUCACCAACUUUGACAACUUUGCCUUCGCCAUGCUCACGGUGUUCCAGUGCAUCACCAUGGAGGGCUGGACGGACGUGCUGUACUGGAUGCAGGACGCUAUGGGCUAUGAGUUACCCUGGGUGUAUUUUGUCAGUCUGGUCAUCUUUGGAUCCUUUUUCGUUCUAAAUCUGGUUCUCGGUGUGUUGAGCGGAGAGUUUUCCAAAGAGAGGGAGAAGGCCAAGGCCCGGGGAGAUUUCCAGAAGCUGCGGGAGAAGCAGCAGCUAGAAGAGGAUCUCAAAGGCUACCUGGAUUGGAUCACUCAGGCCGAAGACAUCGAUCCUGAGAAUGAGGACGAAGGCAUGGAUGAGGAGAAGCCCCGAAACAGAGGCACUCCGGCGGGCAUGCUUGAUCAGAAGAAAGGGAAGUUUGCUUGGUUUAGUCACUCCACAGAAACCCAUGUGAGCAUGCCCACCAGUGAGACCGAGUCCGUCAACACCGAAAACGUGGCUGGAGGUGACAUCGAGGGAGAAAACUGCGGGGCCAGGCUGGCUAAGGGAAGCAGAAGUGCAGUGGAGCCUGCUGUUCUGUUGCCUUGGGGUGUCACGACUGUAAACUCACCCUGGCCUCUGGAAGAACUGCAAACAGAGGCUCUGAGUCAGACCAGUCCCAGCCACCGGAUCUCCAAGUCAAAGUUCAGCCGCUACUGGCGCCGGUGGAAUCGGUUCUGCAGAAGGAAGUGCCGCGCCGCAGUCAAGUCUAAUGUCUUCUACUGGCUGGUGAUUUUCCUGGUGUUCCUCAACACGCUCACCAUUGCCUCUGAGCACUACAACCAGCCCAACUGGCUCACAGAAGUCCAAGACACGGCAAACAAGGCCCUGCUGGCCCUGUUCACGGCAGAGAUGCUCCUGAAGAUGUACAGCCUGGGCCUGCAGGCCUACUUCGUGUCCCUCUUCAACCGCUUUGACUGCUUCGUCGUGUGUGGCGGCAUCCUGGAGACCAUCCUGGUGGAGACCAAGAUCAUGUCCCCACUGGGCAUCUCCGUGCUCAGAUGCGUCCGGCUGCUGAGGAUUUUCAAGAUCACGAGGUACUGGAACUCCUUGAGCAACCUGGUGGCAUCCUUGCUGAACUCUGUGCGCUCCAUCGCCUCCCUGCUCCUUCUCCUCUUCCUCUUCAUCAUCAUCUUCUCCCUCCUGGGGAUGCAGCUCUUUGGAGGAAAGUUCAACUUUGAUGAGAUGCAGACCCGGAGGAGCACAUUCGAUAACUUCCCCCAGUCCCUCCUCACUGUGUUUCAGAUCCUGACCGGGGAGGACUGGAAUUCGGUGAUGUAUGAUGGGAUCAUGGCUUAUGGCGGCCCCUCUUUUCCAGGGAUGUUAGUCUGUAUUUACUUCAUCAUCCUCUUCAUCUGUGGAAACUAUAUCCUACUGAAUGUGUUCUUGGCCAUUGCUGUGGACAACCUGGCUGAUGCUGAGAGCCUCACAUCUGCCCAAAAGGAGGAGGAAGAGGAGAAGGAGAGAAAGAAGCUGGCCAGGACUGCCAGCCCAGAGAAGAAACAAGAGUUGGUGGAGAAGCCGGCAGUGGGGGAAUCCAAGGAGGAGAAGAUUGAGCUGAAAUCCAUCACGGCUGACGGAGAGUCUCCACCCGCCACCAAGAUCAACAUGGAUGACCUCCAGCCCAAUGAAAAUGAGGAUAAGAGCCCCUACCCCAACCCAGAAACUACAGGAGAAGAGGAUGAGGAGGAGCCAGAGAUGCCUGUCGGCCCUCGCCCACGACCACUCUCUGAGCUUCACCUUAAGGAAAAGGCAGUGCCCAUGCCAGAAGCCAGCGCGUUUUUCAUCUUCAGCUCUAACAACAGGUUUCGCCUCCAGUGCCACCGCAUUGUCAAUGACACGAUCUUCACCAACCUGAUCCUCUUCUUCAUUCUGCUCAGCAGCAUUUCCCUGGCUGCUGAGGACCCGGUCCAGCACACCUCCUUCAGGAACCAUAUUCUGUUUUAUUUUGAUAUUGUUUUUACCACCAUUUUCACCAUUGAAAUUGCUCUGAAGAUGACUGCUUAUGGGGCUUUCUUGCACAAGGGUUCUUUCUGCCGGAACUACUUCAACAUCCUGGACCUGCUGGUGGUCAGCGUGUCCCUCAUCUCCUUUGGCAUCCAGUCCAGUGCAAUCAAUGUCGUGAAGAUCUUGCGAGUCCUGCGAGUACUCAGGCCCCUGAGGGCCAUCAACAGGGCCAAGGGGCUAAAGCAUGUGGUUCAGUGUGUGUUUGUCGCCAUCCGGACCAUCGGGAACAUCGUGAUUGUCACCACCCUGCUGCAGUUCAUGUUUGCCUGCAUCGGGGUCCAGCUCUUCAAGGGAAAGCUGUACACCUGUUCAGACAGUUCCAAGCAGACAGAGGCGGAAUGCAAGGGCAACUACAUCACGUACAAAGACGGGGAGGUUGACCACCCCAUCAUCCAACCCCGCAGCUGGGAGAACAGCAAGUUUGACUUUGACAAUGUUCUGGCAGCCAUGAUGGCCCUCUUCACCGUCUCCACCUUCGAAGGGUGGCCAGAGCUGCUGUACCGCUCCAUCGACUCCCACACGGAAGACAAGGGCCCCAUCUACAACUACCGUGUGGAGAUCUCCAUCUUCUUCAUCAUCUACAUCAUCAUCAUCGCCUUCUUCAUGAUGAACAUCUUCGUGGGCUUCGUCAUCGUCACCUUUCAGGAGCAGGGGGAGCAGGAGUACAAGAACUGUGAGCUGGACAAGAACCAGCGACAGUGCGUGGAAUACGCCCUCAAGGCCCGGCCCCUGCGGAGGUACAUCCCCAAGAACCAGCACCAGUACAAAGUGUGGUACGUGGUCAACUCCACCUACUUCGAGUACCUGAUGUUCGUCCUCAUCCUGCUCAACACCAUCUGCCUGGCCAUGCAGCACUACGGCCAGAGCUGCCUGUUCAAAAUCGCCAUGAACAUCCUCAACAUGCUCUUCACUGGCCUCUUCACCGUGGAGAUGAUCCUGAAGCUCAUUGCCUUCAAACCCAAGGGUUACUUUAGUGAUCCCUGGAAUGUUUUUGACUUCCUCAUCGUAAUUGGCAGCAUAAUUGACGUCAUUCUCAGUGAGACUAAUCACUAUUUCUGUGAUGCAUGGAAUACAUUUGACGCCUUGAUUGUUGUGGGUAGCAUUGUUGAUAUAGCAAUCACCGAGGUAAACCCAGCUGAACAUACCCAAUGCUCUCCCUCUAUGAACGCAGAGGAAAACUCCCGCAUCUCCAUCACCUUCUUCCGCCUGUUCCGGGUCAUGCGUCUGGUGAAGCUGCUGAGCCGUGGGGAGGGCAUCCGGACGCUGCUGUGGACCUUCAUCAAGUCCUUCCAGGCCCUGCCCUAUGUGGCCCUCCUGAUCGUGAUGCUGUUCUUCAUCUACGCGGUGAUCGGGAUGCAGGUGUUUGGGAAAAUUGCCCUGAAUGAUACCACAGAGAUCAACCGGAACAACAACUUUCAGACCUUCCCCCAGGCCGUGCUGCUCCUCUUCAGGUGUGCCACCGGGGAGGCCUGGCAGGACAUCAUGCUGGCCUGCAUGCCAGGCAAGAAGUGUGCCCCAGAGUCCGAGCCCAGCAACAGCACGGAGGGUGAAACACCCUGUGGUAGCAGCUUUGCUGUCUUCUACUUCAUCAGCUUCUACAUGCUCUGUGCCUUCCUGAUCAUCAACCUCUUUGUAGCUGUCAUCAUGGACAACUUUGACUACCUGACAAGGGACUGGUCCAUCCUUGGUCCCCACCACCUGGAUGAGUUUAAAAGAAUCUGGGCAGAGUAUGACCCUGAAGCCAAGGGUCGUAUCAAACACCUGGAUGUGGUGACCCUCCUCCGGCGGAUUCAGCCGCCACUAGGUUUUGGGAAGCUGUGCCCUCACCGCGUGGCUUGCAAACGCCUGGUCUCCAUGAACAUGCCUCUGAACAGCGACGGGACAGUCAUGUUCAAUGCCACCCUGUUUGCCCUGGUCAGGACGGCCCUGAGGAUCAAAACAGAAGAGGGACCCAGCCCAUCAGAGGCCCACCAAGGGGCUGAGGAUCCUUUCCGCCCUGCAGGGAACCUAGAACAAGCCAAUGAGGAGCUGCGGGCGAUCAUCAAGAAGAUCUGGAAGCGGACCAGCAUGAAGCUGCUGGACCAGGUGGUGCCCCCUGCAGGUGAUGAUGAGGUCACCGUUGGCAAGUUCUACGCCACGUUCCUGAUCCAGGAGUACUUCCGGAAGUUCAAGAAGCGCAAAGAGCAGGGCCUUGUGGGCAAGCCCUCCCAGAGGAACGCGCUGUCUCUGCAGGCUGGCUUGCGCACACUGCAUGACAUCGGGCCUGAGAUCCGACGGGCCAUCUCUGGAGAUCUCACCGCUGAGGAGGAGCUGGACAAGGCCAUGAAGGAGGCUGUGUCCGCUGCUUCUGAAGAUGACAUCUUCAGGAGGGCCGGUGGCCUGUUCGGCAACCACGUCAGCUACUACCAAAGCGACGGCCGGAGCGCCUUCCCCCAGACCUUCACCACUCAGCGCCCGCUGCACAUCAACAAGGCGGGCAGCAGCCAGGGCGACACUGAGUCGCCAUCCCACGAGAAGCUGGUGGACUCCACCUUCACCCCGAGCAGCUACUCGUCCACCGGCUCCAACGCCAACAUCAACAACGCCAACAACACCGCCCUGGGUCGCCUCCCUCGCCCCGCCGGCUACCCCAGCACGGUCAGCACUGUGGAGGGCCACGGGCCCCCCUUGUCCCCUGCCAUCCGGGUGCAGGAGGUGGCGUGGAAGCUCAGCUCCAACAGGAUGCACUGCUGUGACAUGCUGGAUGGUGGGACCUUCCCUCCCGCCCUGGGCCCCCGCAGGGCUCCUCCCUGUCUGCAUCAGCAGCUCCAGGGUUCCCUGGCGGGGCUGAGAGAGGACACACCCUGCAUCGUGCCUGGCCACGCUUCACUGUGCUGCUCUUCCAGAGUAGGAGAGUGGCUCCCAGCAGGCUGCACAGCCCCCCAGCAUGCCAGGGAAAGGCACGUUCCGAUGUGUGAGGAUCUGGAGCUCAGGAGGGAUUCAGGCUCAGCAGGGACUCAGGCUCACUGCCUUCUGCUCAGGAGAGCAAACCCCUCUAGGUGCCACUCCCGGGAGAGCCAGGCAGCCAUGGCGGGUCAGGAGGAGACGUCUCAGGAUGAGACCUAUGAAGUGAAGAUGAACCAUGACACGGAGGCCUGCAGUGAGCCCAGCCUGCUCUCCACAGAGAUGCUCUCCUACCAGGAUGACGAAAAUCGGCAACUGACGCUCCCAGAGGAGGACAAGAGGGACAUCCGGCAAUCUCCGAAGAGGGGUUUCCUCCGCUCUGCCUCACUAGGUCGAAGGGCCUCCUUCCACCUGGAAUGUCUGAAGCGACAGAAGGACCGAGGGGGAGACAUCUCUCAGAAGACAGUCCUGCCCUUGCAUCUGGUUCAUCAUCAGGCAUUGGCAGUGGCAGGCCUGAGCCCCCUCCUCCAGAGAAGCCAUUCCCCUGCCUCAUUCCCUAGGCCUUUUGCCACCCCACCAGCCACACCUGGCAGCCGAGGCUGGCCCCCACAGCCCGUCCCCACCCUGCGGCUUGAGGGGGUCGAGUCCAGUGAGAAACUCAACAGCAGCUUCCCAUCCAUCCACUGCGGCUCCUGGGCUGAGACCACCCCCGGUGGCGGGGGCAGCAGCGCCGCCCGGAGAGUCCGGCCCGUCUCCCUCAUGGUGCCCAGCCAGGCUGGGGCCCCAGGGAGGCAGUUCCACGGCAGUGCCAGCAGCCUGGUGGAAGCGGUCUUGAUUUCAGAAGGACUGGGGCAGUUUGCUCAAGAUCCCAAGUUCAUCGAGGUCACCACCCAGGAGCUGGCCGACGCCUGCGACAUGACCAUAGAGGAGAUGGAGAGCGCGGCCGACAACAUCCUCAGCGGGGGCGCCCCACAGAGCCCCAAUGGCGCCCUCUUACCCUUUGUGAACUGCAGGGACGCGGGGCAGGACCGAGCCGGGGGCGAAGAGGACGCGGGCUGUGUGCGCGCGCGGGGUCGACCGAGUGAGGAGGAGCUCCAGGACAGCAGGGUCUACGUCAGCAGCCUGUAGUGGGCGCUGCCAGAUGCGGGCUUUUUUUUAUUUGUUUCAAUGUUCCUAAUGGGUUCGUUUCAGAAGUGCCUCACUGUUCUCGUGACCUGGAGUUAACCGGAACAGCGUCUUCAUUCAUUUCUGUUGGGACCAGACGCGGAGCCUGGGUGCGCGAGCCGCCCUCCGGGAGGAAGGCGCCCGGCUGCGUCUGCAGAGGCGGGGAGAGGAGGCGGCGAGGGUCCCGGGGCGCGAGGAAGGCGCCUGCCCUCUCCCAGCUCGCAGGCCCCGGGCCCGGCCGCGCCUCCGCGGGGAGAGCACCCCGGCUUCCCGCGCGCCCUCACCAAAAGGACCCUACAGCAAACGGGUGUCUUUCGACUCUGCUUGUAGAAACCAUUUGCACAUAUUCUGUACGAGCCUCGCUGUCUCCCUAGAGCCAGGGCCCUGCGGAUUUGGAGAAGGGAGCGGGGCAGGACUUCCAGGAGGACCCCAACCCGGCCCGGAGAGGGAGGAGGAGGCCUCCAGGGGCGCGGAGCUCUGGGGAUGGGCGUCGGGCCGGCAGUGGUGCGGCUCACUCCGUCCCUGCCCACCUGCGACGGGAUCCCCCGACCGGCACGGGCCACGCCGAGCUCCCGGCCAGCCGCCGGCCCGCAGGCAGCGCGAGGGAGGAGCUGCGCCGCCGGCUCCGCCCAACCAGGUGGUGCUGAGCUUCCGCUGAGCGCUCUUUUGUUUUGUGGUUUGACACUUUUCUUGACAGCAUGUUGCAGUUUCUUUUCGGUUUUGGUUUUUUUUAAAUGUUUUAUUUUGCUUUCCCAGCGGGAGGGGAGGAAGAAGAGUGUUUACAAAGUCCUGUAGCCCCCUCACCUUUCUGUUUUCACUUUUGCCAAUGUACAUCGGGUUUGGUUUUCUUGUAUUAUUUAAACGGUUGUGGUUUCCUUUUUCCACGGAGGUUCAAUAGAAGCCGCUGCAGGAGAGUUUUACCAACCAUUGUGUAUGCCCAAUAAUUUGUUAUCAUUUCCUUAGGUAGUAACCUAUUUUUGUUCUGGUUUGGUUCGGUUAUCUAAUGGAAAGGUAACUGGCAAUGCACUUGAUGUGGUCUUGCACAUGUGGGUGAUAGAGUUGGGUUCCUUUUUAUGCUGGGUGUACAGGUGGGUUUGGGAGAGAGGAGCAUGCGCGAGAGAGUCUCCGAGUGUGUGCGACGCGUGUGUGUGUGGUGGGUUGUCUGUGUGCAUAUGUCCUGCCCGUGUAUAUGCACCCACACCAUGUGCCCGUGCACACCAGUGACUACGCAGUCCCCCCUUUCUGGUUUAGCUGUGGGAAGAUCUGAAUCUGGGGCCGUUUGAAAGCAAAAACAAACCACUGUCUCUGCUUCUGAAACGGGAAUCAGUAACUCUUUGCAUUUUCUGUCCCACAAGAUAUGCAAAAACAAUGCAAUAAUAUUCAUUUAAAAAUACAAUUGUGAGUUGUGUUGGCAUUAAAACUGUAUUUUAAAAAAAGACAGAAAUUUAAGGGAAAAACACAAGAAGGCAUUUUGCUUCAAUAUAUUCCGUGUAAUGUUUUAUUGCAUUGAUAAUGUUUCUGUUGAAGAAACCGUUAUACUUGAAUUCAGGUCAGUUUCAGUAUUUUUCAAAUAUUUUUUUAAAACUGAAUUGCAAUUGUGCCAAGCGAAUAUAAUGAAUUGAAUUAAGUUGGUUUUCGGAUUCACUUCUUGUAUAUUUUGCUGCAUGUAAAGUAAAUCAUUUUGUAUUUGGAGUGUGACAAGCUUUACCUUUGAACUCAAGUGCUUUUCUAUAUGUGGUUGGGGGAAAGGGAACAAGUUUUCUUUAGUUUGCACAAUGAGCAAAGGUAUCACCAGUGUAGUCAUUAUUCUGCUCUCCACAAACAGGUUUGGACAUUACUGUUUUGCAUAUCUUGUGUUUGCUUACAUUUCCCUCAAUUUUUCCAAAAUCGUUUGCUGGGUAUGUUUGUACCGCCUCUUGCUGUGAGAGACCAGGACCUAUUUUAUUCCAGUCUUCACUCUGUCCACUCUGCUCUGGUCAUCUGAUUUGGUACUUCUCCAAGAACAGCCCUUCACUGUGAGGUGCAGGGAGGCGUUCUGAUGAGCCCUCAGUCACUGGGCCGUCAUCCGCAUCCCCCAUGGAAGAGGUAGCUGGCUUUCCCUUCCCUUCCACCACACGGAAUUUUCUCUUUGGCUUCCUUAGGAAAGUGUACACUAACCGGGAGGAUAAAAUUAAAGUCAGGCUGCUUGGAGGGAGGGGCAUCCUCACUUCCGGAUUCUUGUUGCUCUACCCAACAAGGACAGCAGGGGCUCGAGAAAGGAACUGGUGAAACCCUGAUCCAUCUGAAAGUCAACUCUGCGUGCUCCUUUCUCCAUCCCUUCCUCACUCUGGAGCAGCCUUUCCUUCAGGCUUGCCCUAAUGUUUGGGCUGCCGGGGAGGGGGCCAGGACAAGGGAAGAGGCAUCCGGAGCUCACAGUGGGGGUGGGAACAGAUUUUUGUGGGGGCAUCUCUAAUGCUCACUUAUAUCUCCCUAGAACAUCACUCUUUUGGUGCUGUGUCCUUCAAAUGUAUGUCAACAGUGGUGGCUGAAAAGGGACUGCUUUGGGGAAAACAGGACCCAACCAUUCACCCAGAAUUGACCCAUUAAAUCUCUUCCAGUCCUAGUGUUCCCUGAGCCCCUCUUGGCACAUAUAUAAGUAAGCUAGAAAUUACAAUAAGGGACAGUCCAUUCCUCUAUGACAGCUUGCUGGACUGAUUCAUGACAAAGUGGAGAAAUGUACUCAAUACUCCCCGGUUAACACAGUCUAGAAACAGAGUUUCUUUAUGGAUAUCCACACCCAAGUCAUCCAAACUUUCUUGAUUCCUUUUCACUGCCAUCAAGGUCCUCUAGAAAUUGAGUUUAGGUAUCAUCCUUUGAAAAGUUCCCAAGAUUUCUACCAGGAGGUACACACAGGCGUUCCCUGUCUAGGGCAGGAGGACUAUCCUAGCUUGACCUUCUGAUCCACUAGAAUAAGACUGGCGUAUGAUGCCUGUCAUCAGAACAGACUGGCACAAGUAGUGACAUCAAUGAACCACAGCACAAUCUUCCAAGUGAUGUCUACUCUCCACCUAAAAUGGAAUUUUCCCCAUGACCUUGUAAAACAUAAUUGUCACAUCUUCCAUACCCCUCCUGACAGCCCCCAAGUGUCAGGAGAAAACAGUCAGGGGCUAAGGGCCCAAGGGACUUGAAGAAACAACAGUUUAAGGUCUGCAGUUUGGUCAACUUAAUUCUUGUCCUCCGACCAGCCCUGCCUCUUUCAUUUCCAGACCUUGGAGAAUUUUUCCCAGCUUUGAUUCAGAAGGUACUAGUUAUAACCCCUUUCCUUCUUCUUAAUCCAAUAGGCCUCACUCUCACUGGGAAAUCCACUCAAAGGAACAAGGCAAUGUCUCUCAUUCUAUUUCCCAGUUCCAAAUUCCAGGUGCUUGUCUGGAGUGAAGCUACCCGUUACUUUCUCCCAGCUUUUCUCCACCCAGCAUGUCUCCUGCCCAUGCAGCUGAAGACAGUGGGGCAACCUCAGGAGAAGCAGACCUUUCCAUGCCCAAGUUCAUCUCCUGAGCAACAGUGACACCUAGAAAAUGAGGACUUUGGAAGUCACCCAAAAGAUGGUGGCUACUUUAUGGAGUCCUGAAGAUACACAGCCACCACUCCUAAAGGCAAAGAAAGAAAACACGAAUGUAGGUCAGGGAUAGAGUGGAACCCUGGUCAUCGGGGUUUUUAGCCUCAUCGUGGGAAAGGUGGUAAAGGAGGAUGAUGGCAUCUCCAUCCCUAGAGGCCAAGAAUUGAAAUAUCAUUGUCAAGGAUUAGAAACAAUUCAGCAAAGAGGCCACAAAAAGGGCCUGCUGACUCCCAGAAGACCUCUUUAAACCCCAGGGGAGGCAAAUACUUGCUGAUGGAGUCUGGGCCGUUUCCAUAUUUUAAAGAAGACCUGCCUCUGGGGCAAAUGUCAGCACAGAGAGGACUGGGAGGAGAAUGGAGGCAAGAAAAGGGCAUAUUUUGACUCCCUCUGUGCCUCUUCCCAGUUCAUGGAAGGAUGUGUUCAGCUUACCCACCCACAGUGACCAGUGUGGUGGAGCCGCUGACAUCUCAAGGAUCUAUUUGGGAAGGUGAGAAGAGUACUCAUUCCAUCUGGGGGUGUUGUUCCAGCCACAUCAGCCUACCUGGUGGGAUGUGGGGGUGUCUGCCACCCUGUCCCCCCUCUGCUGAUGUCCCUCCCCUCAGGCUGUCCAGGUGCCACCUGACACAGGCUGCUGUGCAAAGACAGGCGGGGAAGCCCAAACCUCACUCCCAGGGAGGCCCUCAGCCGCCAGAGUCCAGGUUCUCCAGAGGCUACGAUUUGAGGAGGUUGAGGGGGAAGACAGGAGGGAAAGAAAAGUCCUACAACUGUCAGGAAUGGGGCACCUUUCCCUGUCCCUAAGCAAAGCUCCCUCUUCCCACUGCCCUCCCCAGCCCCAGCUCCCUGUCCUCCCCAACACCUAGUGAGAAAGACGGUGCGUGGAAGGGAGUCCCAUGGGCAGAUGCUUACACGACCUCUUUGUGAAGCCUCUUCUGGGUUUAACUUCAUUCAUCAAUUUAUUCUUAUGUCAAAGCAAUGAAACUUUUCUUUCUGGAGCCAGAUACCAAUACAACAGGUGAACGGGUUUCUGCCACAUCUCUACAUUGACGGGGGAUGCUUGAACAACCCCCCUCACUACACAGACACACACCGUUAAGGCACAAGGGCUGGGGUUGAGCUCUAGAUGAGGGACUUUCCUGCUCCUGCAAGGGUGAGCACUGUAUACACAGACAAGGAGGGUGCAGUAGAGUGACUCCCUUGGAUGGAAGUAGUACCAUCAGAACCUACUAUUAUUAUGACAUAAAUUCUAUUUACAUACAUUGAGAGAAUACUACAAUCAACACUUUUUCCUGGGAUGACUUUAAGAGGUUUGAGCCACAGCACCUGAAGUGGCAAAGAUCCAUGGUCUUUGUAGGGUAUUAGAGAACUCUUCCAGUCACCUCUGAAAGCACUCUAGAUCUUGCAGCUGAGUGGAUGAAGUGUAACAAAUCUGUUGCACGCUGAGAGGAGUCAGAAUUAGCAUUUUUCAUGAAAGUUCCCCACGUCUCUACUAAGAAUGAGGAAGAAAAGACUAAGACUAGGUAAUUACACAGAGGCUUGAAAUGUUACAUCACCAGAGCCAAGUCCUCUCCCUUCAGAUCAGUUACUGGCUGCUACACAGGGACACCCCCACCUUUUCAGGGCAUCCCAUGCACUCCACUUCUCAGGAUCUAAGGAAUUUGACUUUGUAGGGAUCCCAGAAAGGGCACUGUGCCACUUCCCCUGGUGUGAAUCAGACAUACAUUGUACAUUCAUUUCUAAAAUUCACUCAUGCACCUCAAACCAAGGUCAUUAUCCAAAAAAAAAAAAAAAAAGCUCUGGGUGGAAGAGUUUGUAAGUUUUAAGAGAGGGUCAUUUCUAUGUGAGGAAAUGCAGAAAUGGACAGAAUGAUUCUUAUUCACUGUUUGGGUCUGGAGAAUUCCCAUUGUGGAAAUCUUAGAGAUCUCAAGUUUAUUACCAAGGGAAUAAGGAAAAAAAGGUGAGCAGGCACCAGGCCAAGCAGUGGCUCCCUUGCCAAGGAACCUGAGGCUGCAGGUUUCAGGGACCCCCUUGAAGAAACCUCUCCUGGCCAUUGGCCAGGAGAAAAGAGAAGUCUCUCCUGUAGAGUCACAAGAGAAGCAAAAGAGGGUGGGUCACUGGGUCCUGGACAUAGCCCCCAACCCCAAGACUUCCCAAUAUGGAGAAACUACACCAAUGUUUAAAAGGGGAAAAGGAAAGAACUUGUACAUCAAGGGAAGAUGAUUUGUAAACACACAGUCCUGUGCAGAAAGAUCCCCUUCAGGAGGUGUCUCCAGCAUCCCAAAGCUGUGCGCACCUUCUCUUUUCCUGCCUCAGGCCACCUAUGCAUCCAGCUGCAGCCCAUACCCACACCUGAAAUCCAUCUCUUGAAUCCCAGCCAGGUUAUAUACCACCCCAUUGCCAUGUCCUGUCCUGGCCAGAAUGCAUGCUGUUCCCCCAAGCCUCGUGGGAGUGAGGCCAUGGGAAACAGAGAUGAGCAUGUCUGGACAAGUCUGUGAUGGUAGUGGAUGAGAAUAACCCAUGGCAAAACACGCACAUUCAUUAAGAAAUAGGGCGACAGAUUCCCCGUUGGUGAAGCACUGAAAGGUCUAUUACUCUCAUAAUAUUGCUGUUUUAUUUUAAUCCACCAGAGCUACCAUGCAAAACUUUCCUCCUGUGAAACGCUCCAGAUAAAGCUCCUCUAAUCUCCCCUUCCCUCAUGUCCUCCAGCUCAAACCCACCUUCAUCCCCCAAACCAAUCUGUAUCAUGCCUGUUAUCAGAGAGGCACAGAAAGAUGGGCAGUGCCUCCGUUGUCACCAUUCCCCACACCCCUACACACCCCCACACCCUCCCCUCCAGGCUCCACGACUUCACAGUCUUACUGUUGUAAAUAUCAUUGUACAGUUUGUAAUCCUCAAAUAAUCCCAUUGUCAGAGGCCUCGCCUGAUGGGCCUUCUCACCCUCGAGAAAGGCCAGGGAAUCUAGAAGGGGCAACCCUUCAAGGAGAGCUUCAGGGUCAUCUCUGUGUGAGACACUAUUGUAUAUUCCUGUAAGAUUGCAUUUUUAUCUAAGGAAUGAUGUUAUUUAAAAAACAAACAAAAAACACAAAAAAUAAGAAUUGCAAAUAAAUUUCUUAACAAUGUCUA